GCCUCCUCCGCCCCGCGCCCUGCGGUGCUGCAGCUGCGGGCGGCUCCAGCUGCCCCCAGAUGUGGGCUGGGCGGCUCGCGGGGAACUUUCGCGCCGGCUGCGAGUGCGGGGCCCCGGCUGCAGUCCGGCUGCCAUGGAUCCGCCGGCGGGAGCCGCUCGCCGCCUGCUCUGCCCCGCGCUGCUGCUGCUGCUGCUGCUGCUGCCGCCGCCGCUCCUGCCGCCGCCGCCGCCGCCCGCGAACGCCAGGCUCGCCGCCGCCGCCGACCCCCCAGGCGGGCCCCUGGGGCACGGAGCGGAGCGCAUCCUGGCGGUGCCCGUGCGCACUGACGCCCAGGGCCGCUUGGUGUCCCACGUGGUGUCGGCAGCUACGUCCAGAGCAGGGGUACGAGCCCGCAGGGCCGCCCCGGUCCGGACCCCGAGCUUCCCCGGAGGCAACGAGGAGGAGCCUGGCAGUCACCUCUUCUACAAUGUCACGGUCUUUGGCCGAGACCUGCACCUGCGGCUGCGGCCCAACGCCCGCCUCGUGGCGCCCGGGGCCACUAUGGAGUGGCAGGGCGAGAAGGGCACCACCCGCGUGGAGCCCCUGCUCGGGAGCUGUCUCUACGUCGGAGACGUGGCCGGCCUAGCCGAAGCCUCCUCUGUGGCGCUCAGCAACUGCGAUGGGCUGGCUGGUCUGAUCCGGAUGGAGGAGGAGGAGUUCUUCAUCGAACCCUUGGAGAAGGGGCUGGCGGCGCAGGAGGCUGAGCAAGGCCGUGUGCAUGUGGUGUAUCGCCGGCCACCCACGUCCCCUCCUCUCGGGGGGCCACAGGCCCUGGACACAGGUGAGGCCUGCAUGGGCAGGCUGUGUGAGAGCCCUCUGGCCCUGGUCCCAGGGGAGCAUCCCCUGUAUGUCGACCCGGGUCUGAGCACUGGUGGAGGCAGAGAGGGAAGAUGGGGAUGAG